GAGGCACAGCUCGUGGGCCUGGGCGGAAGGAUGCGGGGCCGCCUGGGGCCGGGCUCCCGCCCCAGCAGCGGAGGUAACGGCGCCACGGGGUAACGGGCUGGAGGCGCCACAGGGAGCGGCUGGCGCUGGCAAGCGAAGCUUGGGGGUGGGGAGGAGGUAGAGUGAGCCCUCAGUAGGAGGGACGAGGGCAGGGGUCUGACUGCCUCCCCGGGACCGCCCCCACCUCCUCUCUAUCAGGGCCCCCUCCCCCCAUCCCUGUCUCACCGGGCGCGGGGGACGGGGCUAGAGCGGAGUUAGAGCAAGAAGAAUUUCCACCCCUGGAUUCCCUCUGAAACCCUAGAUCGGGUGGUGGAGCCACAGUGUUAAAGAACAGAGAAGUGAUCCUUAAUCAUUUAGAAUUUUGCCUCCACCAUCCACCAGAAAAUGAAGUGGAAAGAGAAGUUGGGGGAUGGUGUCUAUGACACCUUCAUGAUGAUAGAUGAAACCAAAUGUCCCCCCUGUUCAAAUGUACUCUGCAAUCCUUCUGAACCACCUCCACCCAGAAGACUAAAUAUGACCACUGAGCAGUUUACAGGAGAUCAUACUCAGCACUUUUUGGAUGGAGGUGAGAUGAAGGUAGAACAGCUGUUUCAAGAAUUUGGCAACAGAAAAUCCAAUACUAUUCAGUCAGAUGGCAUCAGUGACUCUGAAAAAUGCUCUCCUACUGUUUCUCAGGGUAAAAGUUCAGAUUGCUUGAAUACAGUAAAAUCCAACAGUUCAUCCAAGGCACCCAAAGUGGUGCCUCUGACUCCAGAACAAGCCCUGAAGCAAUAUAAACACCACCUCACUGCCUAUGAGAAACUGGAAAUAAUUAAUUAUCCAGAAAUUUACUUUGUAGGUCCAAAUGCCAAGAAAAGACAUGGAGUUAUUGGUGGUCCCAAUAAUGGAGGGUAUGAUGAUGCAGAUGGGGCCUAUAUUCAUGUACCUCGAGACCAUCUAGCUUAUCGAUAUGAGGUGCUGAAAAUUAUUGGCAAGGGGAGUUUUGGGCAGGUGGCCAGGGUCUAUGAUCACAAACUUCGACAGUACGUGGCCCUAAAAAUGGUGCGCAAUGAGAAGCGCUUUCAUCGUCAAGCAGCUGAGGAGAUCCGGAUUUUGGAGCAUCUUAAGAAACAGGAUAAAACUGGUAGUAUGAACGUUAUCCACAUGCUGGAAAGUUUCACAUUCCGGAACCAUGUUUGCAUGGCCUUUGAAUUGCUGAGCAUAGACCUUUAUGAGCUGAUUAAAAAAAAUAAGUUUCAGGGUUUUAGCGUCCAGUUGGUACGCAAGUUUGCCCAGUCCAUCUUGCAAUCUUUGGAUGCCCUCCACAAAAAUAAGAUUAUUCACUGCGAUCUGAAGCCAGAAAACAUUCUCCUGAAACACCACGGGCGCAGUUCAACCAAGGUCAUUGACUUUGGGUCCAGCUGUUUCGAGUACCAGAAGCUCUACACAUAUAUCCAGUCUCGGUUCUACAGAGCUCCAGAAAUCAUCUUAGGAAGCCGCUACAGCACACCAAUUGACAUAUGGAGUUUUGGCUGCAUCCUUGCAGAACUUUUAACAGGACAGCCUCUCUUCCCUGGAGAGGAUGAAGGAGACCAGUUGGCCUGCAUGAUGGAGCUUCUAGGGAUGCCACCACCAAAACUUCUGGAGCAAUCCAAACGUGCCAAGUACUUUAUUAAUUCCAAGGGCAUACCCCGCUACUGCUCUGUGACUACCCAGGCAGAUGGGAGGGUUGUGCUUGUGGGGGGUCGCUCACGUAGGGGUAAAAAGCGGGGUCCCCCAGGCAGCAAAGACUGGGGGACAGCACUGAAAGGGUGUGAUGACUACUUGUUUAUAGAGUUCUUGAAAAGGUGUCUUCACUGGGACCCCUCUGCCCGCUUGACCCCAGCUCAAGCAUUAAGACACCCUUGGAUUAGCAAGUCUGUCCCCAGACCUCUCACCACCAUAGACAAGGUGUCAGGGAAACGGGUAGUUAAUCCUGCAAGUGCUUUCCAGGGAUUGGGUUCUAAGCUGCCUCCAGUUGUUGGAAUAGCCAAUAAGCUUAAAGCUAACUUAAUGUCAGAAACCAAUGGUAGUAUACCCCUAUGCAGUGUAUUGCCAAAACUGAUUAGCUAGUGGACAGAGAUAUGCCCAGAGAUGCAUAUGUGUAUAUUUUUAUGAUCUUACAAACCUGCAAAUGGAAAAAAUGCAAGCCCAUUGGUGGAUGUUUUUGUUAGAGUAGACUUUUUUUAAACAAGACAAAACAUUUUUAUAUGAUUAUAAAAGAAUUCUUCAAGGGCUAAUUACCUAACCAGCUUGUAUUGGCCAUCUGGAAUAUGCAUUAAAUGACUUUUUAUAGGUCAAUGCAUCUUUGUUAUUAUCGUCAGAUGUAUUUCAACUGAUGUAUUAUACUAUUGGUUUAAAUCUCUUUCUCUCAAGAUAGAAGGUGUAGCAAAAGUAUCCCAACUACUCCUCGCUUCUAGUGUCCCUCGGCAUCUGUUCUGGAGGGGUAAUUUGGGAUGUGGUGUUAGUUGUGGCUGAGAGCCAGUGCUAGGUCCCUUGCCCCACUAGGCCAUUCUCUAGGCUCAUUCUAGGUGAAAGAGCUCACAGCAGACUGUGGGGUGGGGGAGCACCAGGAAGCUGUUGGUGACCUGGACAACUGGUGUCCCUGGUUUUCAGUGACUCGCUCCUCUUCCCUUCAGUUCUCUGAUGUUUGGUGUUAUUAUUUUAUGUUGUUAUUUUGCCUCUGAUUUGUUUCCUAGUCACUCAAAGCAUUUUACAGAAGCCUUACCACUUUACUAAAUAACCCUGUAAGGUACUGAUUUAAAAACUGAGUCAUAUGCAUCCCUCCUCCUUUCCUCUCCCAUGCCCAAGGAAGAUAAAACAGCUUCUCUGCCACAAUUGACCCAGAGUGGUAAAGAUAGAGAAUCAGCAUGAAAACUGCAGUUCCCCAGCUUUGUGGUACUCCACGGACCAGCCUCCUUGCUGCAUUUUCAUAGAAUCUCUUCCUUAUAAAAGUAAUCACUCUCGGAUAAACCUUACUACAGUUUAAAAAUGCUUCCCUCUUCUCUUUACAGCUACCUGCCACUUCAAUGUGCCACAUUUUUCCCCCCACUUUCACGUUAAGCUUAAUGCUAUUCCCUAGAUCUGAGUGAACUUCAGUUAGAAGAAGAAAACUAAAAAUCCAGAAACUGGUGAUAAUCAAGUUUUCCCUUUUUAUGUUUCUUAAUUUUAUUCUCUUCAACAGCUUUUCUUUUUCUCUGCUAAGAUUUAAACAGUGAGGGCUGAUAAUAAAACUAAUUGUUAAGCCAGUGUCCUACUUACAAGGGUGGAGACGGGACAGAAGCUAACUCACUGCUACUGGGUUUUGUUUGUUGUUUCCUGUCCCUUGCUCUAUUUCUGUCCUCUUCCAGAACAAAAGUAUGCUCAAGUUCUAUCCUAAAUGUGUGCUCUUGGCUGGGUAUUAGUGGCUCAUGCCUGUAAUCCCAGCACUUUGGGAGGCUGAGGUGGGUGGAUUCCUUGAGCCCAGGAGUUCAAGACCAGCCUGGGCAACAUGGUGAAACCCUGCCUCUACAAAAAAUACAAAAAUUAGCCAGGCCUAGUGGCACAUGCCUGUAAUCCCAGCUACUUGGGAGGCUGAGGUGGGAGGAUCACUUGAGCUGAGAUCAUGCCACUGCACUCCAGCCUAGGCAACAGAGUGAGACUCUGUCUAAAAAACAAACCAAAAAAAGUGUGUUCUUUAAAGUAGAAUAUUUGCUUUUUACAAUAUAGUUCUCAGAAUGAUCCAGUUCCAUUUAUUAUUCUAGAAUGUGGUGCAAACUCAAUGACAUUGGAAGAGACUCUUUUUGUUGGGCAGUGUAGGAACAAGAAAAGAAAAUAAAAAUGCCAUGAGUAUAUUAUUUAAGGAACUUUUGUUUUAUCCAAAAGUAGUCAUGAUUGCUGUAGCAUAGGCUGUGAAAAAUGAGAGAGUGCAAAUCUCUCUCAUUUAAAUGUCCACAGUGGCUUUAGUCUCCCAAGUACAAGGGCCAGAUGGCAGAGAACAGCUUAAACUGAGCCUUCAGCCUCAUUAAUAGGAGGAAGUCUUGGUACUUUUGGUGACUAAGAAACUGGAUUAUUUAAAACCUUAAUUAUCUCCUUUACUCCUGGUUUACAGAAGGCAAUAAAUAUACAACUCCUUUAGAUCCCUCUAACUCCUGCUGAAUUUUCUUUCUUUUUUUCUAAGUCUGCAUCCUAUCUCUUGAUUCCAUUGCCUGAAGAAGCUGUGUGAAAUUAGUCUGGUUAUUGGUUUUCUUGUCUGAUAGUGGCAUCUUGAUCUCUUCAGAUGUCACACUAAAUGCUGCUCAUAACCCAUCCUCCUCUUCUUUAUUCAUCACUGCCUUCUUCAAGGGAGGUCUUGAAACUGCCUCAUCUACCUCAUGAUCUGCUAGUCGAGAUAGUGACUCUUUGGAAGUUGGUAGUCCAAUGUCUGCUUCCCCGCAUUAACCACAUUGCGUAGGUUUGGGAAUUUUGCAGGUGCUAAAUCAUCAUGGCCAGGAAGAUGAAACACCUUGAGAAAUGGGAACAUCUCUUCACUGUGUUCUUGGAUCAGCCUUCUUUCAACUACCAAGAAAUGGAUGAUUUCUCUGCCAACUCCAGGAAGUAGUACAGCAUGAUUGAAUCCUUCUUCAGUGAAUCUUUUCAUUGUAACUUAGGGUGUAAAAGCUCAUAUCUACUCAAAAAACUCAAAUCUACUCUUUCAGUAGAUAUGAGCUUACAUUGACUUAUGAAUGGUUUUCCUGUAGGCCCAACAGUGUCAUGACCCUCCAGUUGAAACAAAGCAUGAGUUAUUUUUAUAUCGAGUCCUUGAACUGCUAGCCAGGUAGAUGUUUCCUUGAAGUCCAGAGCAGGAUCCAAGUCAGAUGAAGGAGGUGGCACACCUGGCUUAACUGCAGAUCAGGGAGCAUUGAACCUCUACAAUUUGCUGCAUUGGAUUUCUGCAUGGGUUUCUCACUGAAUAGUAAAUUAGAGAAAAUGCUACUUUUACUAUUUUGCAUUUUAUAUCAACAUUAGCAGCCUGUUCCCACUCAGGUGCUGUCCAAGGCACAUGUUUCCUUGGGAUGUUUGGACAGAAUGAUCUGGCUUGAUGUAUUUCUUGGGCUCUGGUACCACAUCAUAGAGUUGGUUAAAUGUAGCCAGCAGCAGUGUCAAGACAGCUGACACUGUCUUCCAAGAGUGAAUGCAUUGGCCUUUGGAACUGCUGCUAAAGCCAUGUGUGGGGUGGCGAGCACAUCUUUAGGUGGCAGCAAGGCUAUAUCUGAUUGACACAGAUCUGAAGUCUCUAACACCAUAUUGCUGUUGUCCUGAAUUUUCUAACUUGGAGAAAUUUAAGGAUCUCCUGCAUUAUCUAGGCAGAGCAUAUGUUGAGGUUGUUUUGCCAGUUGUUAUCAGUGUUGAAGAACUGCUCCUGUAAGCAAACUGUUAAAAGCAUUACUACCCCAUAUGCAUCUGAUGUACACUGUGUUUUGGUGUUUGUGUUUUUAGUGAGAGUUCUAGCCAGUACUGUGCCUGAACUUGGGAGAGAAAGGGGCCUGUGGCUGAGGUUGGUGCGUGCUCUAUUUCUGUGUAUCGAAUGGACUACAAGGUUACUGAAACUGGGCUAAGGGAAAGUGUAUAGACAACUCAUUACACUGUAGACAGAUUUUAGAAAGCUACAGGAAGGCAAAUGGAUGUUUCUGCCUCAAUUUGGCAACCGAGAGAGUGAUGCAGAGCAGAGUCAUUGAAGUUGGCAUACCUGUCUUCUGCAGGCCAAUUCAAGUUUGAGGAGAGUGGGCUGCUUAAAAACAUGGUGCUCGUCCACAUGGAUUUGAGGAAGUUUAUGGUUGGGUUUCAAGCUUAGGGACAAGUUGUGGUUUUUAGAGGCAGUAACUCUAUGCCACCUUAUUGGCCACUGUUAAAAGUUUCACUUGGAUCCCUGCCCAGCCAUAGCAAUGAGUGACUGAAUUGGAUCAGAGUUAGUACAGAAAUUCAGACUGUCUCUUCCUCAGUUACUGGAUUGUUCUUUAGCCAUUUUUCUUCUAGUCAUUUCAGUCAAACUGGUUAGGUUAGGUGACUUACUGAGUUCUAAAUUGACAAAUUUUAAUUUCCAAGUUGUUUCUGACACGGUGAGAGUUGGGUUAGAAUUUUUAUUUCAUUCCCCAAGUCAUUUUUUCUUUUUCUUUAUUUUUUCUUUUUGAGACAGAGUCUCGCUCUGUCGUCCAGGCUGGAGUGAAGUGGCGCAGUGUUGUCUGCAGCCUCAACCUCCCAGGCUCAGGUGAUUCUCCCAUCUCAACCUCCAGAGUAACUGGGACUACAGUCACGUGCUACCAUGCCUGGCUAAUUUUUUGUAUAUCUGUAGAGAGGGGGUUUCACCAUGUUGCUCGGGCUGGUCUUGAACUCCUGGGCUCAAGUGAUCCAUGUGCCUUACCCUCUCAAAGUGCUGGGAUUAUAGGUGUGAGCGACCGUGCCCAGCCUCAUUUUUUCUUUCAAUAUGGAAAAUUGGCUAAUCCACCUAAUACCUGCUCAUCUUCUAGUAUUCUAUCCUACCAUCUACCCUCAGAGUUAUUGAUGUACUCUUUCAUCAUGUGCUAUCAUGAUUUCUCCUUAGAUUAGAAAGUAAGCUUCAAAUGGGAGUGUGUCUUCAUAUUGUUCUGAAUUAACAGAUUUUGAUGCCCGCUGAUCAUGUGCAGAUGAUGGAAGCUCAUUUCCUUCCAUGAACCAGGAGCAUGCUCGCCUCUUCUUUUAAGUUGACCCACACAAUCUCUGAUGUCUUCUUUUUGGGAAAGGGUAAUGAGAUAAGGAUUAAGGACAUUUUCUUCUGGUCCAGUGUUAGAUACAGUUACCUUGAUAAUAAUGAAAAAAAAAUGAAUACCACCAAAACCUAACUAUGAUGUAAGGAUUCUGCUUCUGCCCCACAGGGGCUCUGAAAGAGUCUAGCCUGGAUCUUCUUUCCCAGAGGAAGUUUGACUUAUGACCAUAUUAGUAUGCUUUAUUCCUUGGUGUUUAAGGGAGUUGGGGCAGACAGGUUAGCUGGCUAAUGUCAUUACAAUUUAGUUUUUGUGACAAUCUGUUAAGAAGGGGGCUUAUUGCAUAAUCAAAAAAGAACAAUAAAAAAAUAAAAAUUUCUACUGUGAAACUAUUUCAAUCUGUAGCAGCUGGUCAUGUUAAAACACUUUCUGUUUUGCUUAAUUCGUAACUAGGCAUAAUUAAAGUUAAAUGCUAAAUUUUAGGUAGCAGCUGAUAAAUGGUUCUAAGCUUUCCUGACAGAAUACUCCUACUACUUUGGUGAAUCAUGGAAAACUCUUUCUCCUUUAUUUUUAAUUAUUUCUUUUCCAUCUGUUAUUGAUGUCAUCAACACGGAAGUUGGAAAGGUGACAAUGAUUGUUCUAGACUGCCUCUGUAAUGCUUUUUCUCCUCUGAGAAUUAAAAAUACAUACUUACACCUUGAGCCAGGUAGAAUUGCCAGAACAUGUUUUCCUCCGUGUCUUCGGUCUAGAUGACCAAUCUGUAGAACGCUAUAACUUACUAUGCGUAGAGCAGCGGCAGGCAUUCAUGCUAUGGAAAACCUGGAGUCAGUACAAAUAAGGAGUAAGAAAAGGCCAGGGAUUGGCAAAUCAAAGAAGAGUUCUCUUCUGCCAGGGAUUAGCCUCCUAGUUUUAAAUAUAUUUUUAAUAUCCCCAUUUUAACAUACUCCAUUUUCACCUUCAACCUAUCCUUCCUGAAGCCCAAACUUUUAAAGAAUUUACUUCCAGACCUGGCCUUCAGCCUAAUAUGAUUAGGGUGUUUUUCUGAGUGUCUGUCAAAUUAUGCUGGCUAAUUUCAAUGAGAAAAGAUUUUAGAGUCACAGUGAACCCAUCCAUAAAAGGACUAAAAGCUCUCUCUGGUCCCUGAGAUCCACAACCCCUGAGAGAAGCCAGAACUACAAAUGCAUCGUCUAGACUUUGAAGAAGCAGGGUAUGAUUCUUAAUAUAGCCCACCCAUCGCUAAGUCAAGCCUAGACUCUAAUAUUUUUCUAUAACAGGAGAAGCCUCCCUGACUGGAGACUAGAGUCUCACAUCUUCUGCCACCACAUGAAUAGACUAAAAAGAAAGGAGAGUCCCACAUCAGGCCAAGUGGUGACCUGUGGCUAUUUCAGCUCAGAAUGUCAGCCUCUGAAGCAUCAGGUUUGAAUGACUUUGGUGUCAUGGGAUUCUGUCCAUUGUCCGUUUGAGUCUGCUGACAUGCUUCCUCUGGAAAGUGCAGUUUGGCAUGGAUGAGUCAGUGGUUUUUUAUUUUGGGGUGUUUUUUAAAAAAUAAAAAUGAAUUGCUUUGAGAA